AAAACAUGGUGCUUUUUGUUUCUGCUGGAGUGCUCAGUCAGAGAGAUUCAGUUCAGCACAAUAUCAAUCAUUACAAAUUCUUCCCCGAAAUUCAAGACACAUUAAUCAAAACAAAUGGAACUCAAGAAAAAUGAAAACUGGGGGGGGUGAAUAAACAAAUACAUGAUUGAGUUGAAAACAUAAAAAUAUUUAUUAAAAUACCAAAAAUAUUAAAUAGAAACAUUCUGAUGUAAUGAUUUCUGAUACAGUUCAAACUUAAAUAAAGAAUGUAUGGUCACAUAAAAUGUAAGUAAGUAUAUCACCUUUCACCUAAAGUUUUCCAGUUAAAUGCAAAACCUUCCUCUUUACCCUAACUAGGUAGAUAAUUAUAUCACUCUGCAUAGUCAUGUUAGGAGUUUAAUUUUCAAGCUAAAUCAAAAUCACUUAAAAUGUCAAUGAUAGUUUAAAAUUUAAGAAUAGAAAUUUGGACAUAUCAAACUCAAAAUUGAUGCUUUAUUGAAAAAAACUAAAUGUCUUUAAAUUGCUAUAACAAACUUUAUAUGUUCAAAAUUAGUUAACAAAAAUAAAAGAGGACAAAUUUCUGCAUUCUUCAACCUCCAAAUUUCUAAUAUCUUUAUUCUAAGAAACUGCAGCUAUUGUAGUGAUAUUCCUUCAAUCCUGAAAACACUCAGGAAGCAAUUUUUUUUAAAUGUUUUACCUUGGCAGGAACUUUAGAUCACAAGUCAAAGGUAUCUCUUCUAAACUUGUAAAGAAAGUAAACAAUCUACCAAGAGAACAAACAGCUCCCAAUAGAUACAGCUCUUACUGCUUCCUCCCCUUAUUUUGUUUCUUUUAGUUAGAGAGCCAUGACAAAGGAAAAACAAAAUAAUUUCAGAUUUAUAUUUCUGUUGCUUCUUUUUUCUUCCUUCCAUUUUGUUCAUUGCAUAAAACAAAUUGAUUAGGAGGUUCUCUUGCUGGGCUUCAAAUAUCAUUAAUAUGUAGAUGACUUCCAAGUAGCUAUCCCCCACUCCUGUCUGACUUCUAAAUUCUGGUCUUAUUUAUUCAAAUGUUUACCUAGUAUCUCCACUUGAAUGUCUAAUGGGAAACUCAAAUAUAAUACGUUCAAAACUAAAUUAUUGGUCAACUCACUUUCCCAUCAAAACUCAAGUUCCCCUUUGUUGAAUAGCAACAUCCUUACACUCUAAUAGCCACCCCAAAAGGCAAACACUCAUCCCUGAAUUCCUCCCUUUUCCUCAUUGUCUGUUCCAAUAUCUCUACAGGUACUAAGCAGUCAAUGUUUAUCUUUCACUGGUUCAUACCCUCCUUGAAGCCAAGAACCAUAUUUCUUGGAUCUGUUAAAUCCCUAGGACCUUUAAAGAUUUUAAAACAAAUAAAAUUACCUAUAUAACAGCUUCUUCAUUUGCUAAGCAAAUGAUUACUUUUACAUACCUACAUUGCAAGUGAUACUGGCACUUCACUGCAUUGAAGAAGUCACUAGAUCUUGAAAGAUAAGCUCUAUUGUAUCCUUCCUCCCAAUUGUUAAAACCCACAGCAGAUAUACAUGAAGAGUGAAUGUUGAUUUAAACUGUGAACUUUAGUUAAUAAUAAUGUAUUAAUAUUAGCUCAUCAAUUGUAACAAAUCGACUACAGUAACGCAAAAUGUUAAUGGAGAAACUAUACAGGAGAGAAGGGAUAUAUGGAAACUCUCUGUACUUUCUGUUCAAUUUUCUUUAAGUCUAAAACUGUUCUGAAAAUAACAUAUAAAAUAUGUCACAGAAAAAAUAUUUCUCUCAUUUUAUGCCAUUGUAUUCUCAAGACAUCUAGAGACCCAUUUUUUCUCCAGUCCCCAAUGCCUUGUCUUUUAAUACCUAACUUUUUAUUUAAUAUUUUAUCUAUUAGCUGAGUAUAUUUCAUUUCCCUUCCCACAAGUGAAAAUAGAUAAUAUAUAAUGCUGGCUUCAUGAAGACUUAUGAAGAAAUCAAUUCUAUGAAAUAAAAAUAUUUCUGAAUGAGUUUAUUACAACUGAGUGGGGAAUUUGAGUGUCAUUUCUAGAGAAUUUGGUCCAUAUAAAUUCAGUCUUGGCAGCUAGCCAUUAGGGGUUUUUGAACUGGCAUAUUUGAGAAGUGUUCUAACUUCUCAGUGGAAUAAAGAAGAGGGGAAAGAACAUUAUAGAAUGAUUCUUUUCUUUAAUAAAUUUCCAUAUAAAAGGGUUUUGAAAGUCUGGCCUCAAGGUAAUUCCAGAAAUAGAUUUCAAAGACUGCGACUCAAGUUUCUGUGUUAUAGUAAGCUUAAGUUUUAUAAAGUGUCAAAUUGAUGAUCAGUUAUAUGGAAGCCUCUAUUUAUAAUAGUAUAGUCCAUUUUUAUACUACUUUUAAUUUGCAAAGGUGCUUUCAUAUAUUAUCUUAUUUGGUAUUCAUAGUCAUCCUGGGAAAAUUGUAGAACAGAUGCUAACUCCUAAAUAGAUAACCACAAUUUCACAAAGUAAAGAAAAAGAAAUGCAUGGAAGUAUCCUCAGUCCAAUUUUAUCAGUCCAUUUUCUAUUGCUUCAAAACACCUGCAACUAGGUAAGUUAUAAAGACAAGAAAUUUAUUUCCUACAGUUAUGGAGGCUGAGAAGUCCAAGGUUGAGGGGCCAUAUCUGGUGAGAGCCUCCUUGCUGGUGGGGACUCCGUAGAGUCCUGUGGCAGCAGCAACACAGGGCGUCAUGUGGUGAAGGGACUGCGUGUGCUCGGGUGUUUGCUCAGGUCUCUCUUCCUCUUCUUGUAGAGCCACCAGGCCUACUCCCAUGAUAACCCAUGAAUCCAUUAAUCCAUGAAUGGAUUAAAAUUCAAUCACCUCUUUAAGGUCUCCUCUUUAAAUACUGUCAUGUUAGGGAAUGUUUCCAACACAUGAAAUCUGGGGGACACAAGAAAACCAUAGCACCAAUGUUAACCAUUUAAUAGUAAUUCUUGUGCUUCAAGAUUUUUUUUUUUUUUUUUUUUGAGACGGAGUCUGGCUCUGUCGCCCAGGCUGGAGUGCAGUGGCGCGAUCUUGGCUCACUGCAAGCUCCGCCUCCCGGGUUCACGCCAUUCUCCUGCCUCAGCCUCCCGAGUAGCUGGGACUACAGGCGGCUGCCACCAUGCCCAGCUAAUUUUUUUUUUUUUGUAUUUUUUUAGUAGAGACGGGGUUUCACCGUGUUAGCCAAGAUGGUCUCGAUCUCCUGACUUCGUGAUCCGCCCGCCUCGACCUCCCAAAGUGCUGGGAUUACAGGCGUGAGCCACCGUGCCCGGCCGCUUCAAGAUUUCUUAAUGAAGGUAGUUGCAUCGAUGUUCAUAGGUGUUUAAAAUUAUCCAACUGCCAUAGAGCUAAAUUCUUUUUUGGAAAAUUGAACCGAACUUCUACUGAAUACAAGAUGAAAAUGUGGUUGCUGGUCAGUCAUCUUGUGAUAAUAUCUAUUACUACCUGUUUAGCAGAGUUUACAUGGUAUAGAAGAUAUGGUCAUGGAGUUUCUGAGGAAGACAAAGGAUUUGGACCAAUUUUUGAAGAGCAGCCAAUCAAUACCAUUUAUCCAGAGGAAUCACUGGAAGGAAAAGUCUCACUCAACUGUAGGGCACGAGCCAGCCCUUUCCCGGUUUACAAAUGGAGAAUGAAUAAUGGGGACGUUGAUCUCACAAGUGAUCGAUACAGUAUGGUAGGAGGAAACCUUGUUAUCAACAACCCUGACAAACAGAAAGAUGCUGGAAUAUACUACUGUUUAGCAUCUAAUAACUACGGGAUGGUCAGAAGCACUGAAGCAACCCUGAGCUUUGGAUAUCUUGAUCCUUUCCCACCUGAGGAACGUCCUGAGGUCAGAGUAAAAGAAGGGAAAGGAAUGGUGCUUCUCUGUGACCCCCCAUACCAUUUUCCAGAUGAUCUUAGCUAUCGCUGGCUUCUAAAUGAAUUUCCUGUAUUUAUCACAAUGGAUAAACGGCGAUUUGUGUCUCAGACAAAUGGCAAUCUCUACAUUGCAAAUGUUGAGGCUUCCGACAAAGGCAAUUAUUCCUGCUUUGUUUCCAGUCCUUCUAUUACAAAGAGCGUGUUCAGCAAAUUCAUCCCACUCAUUCCAAUACCUGAACGAACAACAAAACCAUAUCCUGCUGAUAUUGUAGUUCAGUUCAAGGAUGUAUAUGCAUUGAUGGGCCAAAAUGUGACCUUAGAAUGUUUUGCACUUGGAAAUCCUGUUCCGGAUAUCCGAUGGCGGAAGGUUCUAGAACCAAUGCCAAGCACUGCUGAGAUUAGCACCUCUGGGGCUGUUCUUAAGAUCUUCAAUAUUCAGCUAGAAGAUGAAGGCAUCUAUGAAUGUGAGGCUGAGAACAUUAGAGGAAAGGAUAAACAUCAAGCAAGAAUUUAUGUUCAAGCAUUCCCUGAGUGGGUAGAACACAUCAAUGACACAGAGGUGGACAUAGGCAGUGAUCUCUACUGGCCUUGUGUGGCCACAGGAAAGCCCAUCCCUACAAUCCGAUGGUUGAAAAAUGGAUAUGCGUAUCAUAAAGGGGAAUUAAGACUGUAUGAUGUGACUUUUGAAAAUGCCGGAAUGUAUCAGUGCAUAGCUGAAAACACAUAUGGAGCCAUUUAUGCAAAUGCUGAGUUGAAGAUCUUGGCGUUGGCUCCAACUUUUGAAAUGAAUCCUAUGAAGAAAAAGAUCCUGGCUGCUAAAGGUGGAAGGGUGAUAAUUGAAUGCAAACCUAAAGCUGCACCGAAACCAAAGUUUUCAUGGAGUAAAGGGACAGAGUGGCUUGUCAAUAGCAGCAGAAUACUCAUUUGGGAAGAUGGUAGCUUGGAAAUCAACAACAUUACAAGGAAUGAUGGAGGUAUCUAUACAUGCUUUGCAGAAAAUAACAGAGGGAAAGCUAAUAGCACUGGAACCCUUGUUAUCACAGAUCCUACGCGAAUUAUAUUGGCCCCAAUUAAUGCCGAUAUCACAGUUGGAGAAAACGCCACCAUGCAGUGUGCUGCGUCCUUUGAUCCUGCCUUGGAUCUCACAUUUGUUUGGUCCUUCAAUGGCUAUGUGAUCGAUUUUAACAAAGAGAAUAUUCACUACCAGAGGAAUUUUAUGCUGGAUUCCAAUGGGGAAUUACUAAUCCGAAAUGCGCAGCUGAAACAUGCUGGAAGAUACACAUGCACUGCCCAGACAAUUGUGGACAAUUCUUCAGCUUCAGCUGACCUUGUAGUGAGAGGCCCUCCAGGCCCUCCAGGUGGUCUGAGAAUAGAAGACAUUAGAGCCACUUCUGUGGCACUUACUUGGAGCCGUGGUUCAGACAAUCAUAGUCCUAUUUCUAAAUACACUAUCCAGACCAAGACUAUUCUUUCAGAUGACUGGAAAGAUGCAAAGACAGAUCCCCCAAUUAUUGAAGGAAAUAUGGAGGCAGCAAGAGCAGUGGACUUAAUCCCAUGGAUGGAGUAUGAAUUCCGCGUGGUAGCAACCAAUACACUGGGUAGAGGAGAGCCCAGUAUACCAUCUAACAGAAUUAAAACAGACGGUGCUGCACCAAAUGUGGCUCCUUCAGAUGUAGGAGGUGGAGGUGGAAGAAACAGAGAGCUGACCAUAACAUGGGCGCCUUUGUCAAGAGAAUACCACUAUGGCAACAAUUUUGGUUACAUAGUGGCAUUUAAGCCAUUUGAUGGAGAAGAAUGGAAAAAAGUCACAGUUACUAAUCCUGAUACUGGCCGAUAUGUCCAUAAAGAUGAAACCAUGAGCCCUUCCACUGCAUUUCAAGUUAAAGUCAAGGCCUUCAACAACAAAGGAGAUGGACCUUACAGCCUAGUAGCAGUCAUUAAUUCAGCACAAGACGCUCCCAGUGAAGCCCCAACAGAAGUAGGUGUAAAAGUCUUAUCAUCUUCUGAGAUAUCUGUUCAUUGGGAACAUGUUUUAGAAAAAAUAGUGGAAAGCUAUCAGAUUCGGUAUUGGGCUGCCCAUGACAAAGAAGAAGCUGCAAACAGAGUUCAAGUCACCAGCCAAGAGUACUCGGCCAGGCUCGAGAACCUUCUGCCAGACACCCAGUAUUUUAUAGAAGUCGGGGCCUGCAAUAGUGCAGGGUGUGGACCUCCAAGUGACAUGAUUGAGGCUUUCACCAAGAAAGCACCUCCUAGCCAGCCUCCAAGGAUCAUCAGUUCAGUAAGGUCUGGUUCACGCUAUAUAAUCACCUGGGAUCAUGUCGUUGCACUAUCAAAUGAAUCUACAGUGACGGGAUAUAAGGUACUCUACAGACCUGAUGGCCAGCAUGAUGGCAAGCUGUAUUCAACUCACAAACACUCCAUAGAAGUCCCAAUCCCCAGAGAUGGAGAAUACGUUGUGGAGGUUCGCGCGCACAGUGAUGGAGGAGAUGGAGUGGUGUCUCAAGUCAAAAUUUCAGGUGCACCCACCCUAUCCCCAAGUCUUCUCGGCUUACUGCUGCCUGCCUUUGGCAUCCUUGUCUACUUGGAAUUCUGAAUGUGUUGUGACAGCUGCUGUUCCCAUCCCAGCUCAGAAGACACCCUUCAACCCUGGGAUGACCACAAUUCCUUCCAAUUUCUGCGGCUCCAUCCUAAGCCAAAUAAAUUAUACUUUAACAAACUAUUCAACUGAUUUACAACACACAUGAUGACUGAGGCAUUCGGGAACCCCUUCAUCCAAAAGAAUAAACUUUUAAAUGGAUAUAAAUGAUUUUUAACUCGUUCCAAUAUGCCUUAUAAACCACUUAACCUGAUUCUGUGACAGUUGCAUGAUUUAACCCAAUGGGACAAGUUACAGUGUUCAAUUCAAUACUAUAGGCUGUAGAGUGAAAGUCAAAUCACCAUAUACAGGUGCUUUAAAUUUAAUAACAAGUUGUGAAAUAUAAUAGAGAUUGAAAUGUUGGUUGUAUGUGGUAAAUGUAAGAGUAAUACAGUCUCUUGUACUUUCCUCACUGUUUUGGGUACUGCAUAUUAUUGAAUGGCCCCUAUCAUUCAUGACAUCUUGAGUUUUCUUGAAAAGACAAUAGAGUGUAACAAAUAUUUUGUCAGAAAUCCCAUUAUCAAAUCAUGAGUUGAAAGAUUUUGACUAUUGAAAACCAAAUUCUAGAACUUACUAUCAGUAUUCUUAUUUUCAAAGGAAAUAAUUUUCUAAAUAUUUGAUUUUCAGAAUCAGUUUUUUAAUAGUAAAGUUAACAUACCAUAUAGAUUUUUUUUUACUUUUAUAUUCUACUCUGAAGUUAUUUUAUGCUUUUCUUAUCAAUUUCAAAUCUCAAAAAUCACAGCUCUUAUCUAGAGUAUCAUAAUAUUGCUAUAUUUGUUCAUAUGUGGAGUGACAAAUUUUGAAAAGUAGAGUGCUUCCUUUUUUAUUGAGAUGUGACAGUCUUUACAUGGUUAGGAAUAAGUGACAGUUAAGUGAAUAUCACAAUUACUAGUAUGUUGGUUUUUCUGCUUCAUUCCUAAGUAUUACGUUUCUUUAUUGCAGAUGUCAGAUCAAAAAGUCACCUGUAGGUUGAAAAAGCUACCGUAUUCCAUUUUGUAAAAAUAACAAUAAUAAUAAUAAUAAUAAUUAGUUUUAAGCUCAUUUCCCACUUCAAUGCAAUACUGAAAACUGGCUAAAAAUACCAAAUCAAUAUACUGCUAAUGGUACUUUGAAGAGUAUGCAAAACUGGAAGGCCAGGAGGAGGCAAAUAAUAUGUCUUUCCGAUGGUGUCUCCCAAGUGUUGGUGCUUUGGGUUUUUAUAAGUUGUGAAAAGGAAGAUGCACAUUUCUUCAUUCUCCAUGGUGUGCAUGGAAAUGUGUUUGAGUGUGGAUGUAAAAGAAAUCGAGUAAUAAAGAAUUAGCUGGCUUGUGAAAUAGUGCAGUGUUGGAUGCUUCAAGAGGUAUAAUCCUAUUUUAUUAGCACAAACUUGCUAGCUAAUUAGAGUUUAUCUUUUUAGAAAGGACACCGUAUAGGUUCGUAAAAAAUAUUUACAGGAAGCAAAAUAGAUCUAUUACUACUUUACCGACUUUACCCCCUUUCUUUAAUUUGUAUAAUUUUUGUACUAUAUAUCGAUGUGUAAAUGUUUAGAGUCUUCAUUAUGAAAAUAUCAAUAAAUAUUUCAUUAGUUUACAUUUAACUCUGGUAUAAAAUGAAACUUUUAAAAAUAAGUGAAAUGGAUGAUUUCCCAGUGGAAGUAUGUCAACAGUCUUAAGAUCAUUGCCAGAUUUCAUAAAAUAUUUAAGUAUUUGAAAAAGAAACAAAAUGUCUUCAUACUUUAGGGAAACGAAUACCCUGUAUACCUUCUGUACAAAUGUUUGUGUUUUCAUUGUUACACUUUGGGGUUUUACUUUUGCAAUGUGACCCAUGUUGGGCAUUUUUAUAUAAUCAACAACUAAAUCUUUUGCCAAAUGCAUGCUUGCCUUUUAUUUUCUAAUAUAUGAUAAUAACGAGCAAAACUGGUUAGAUUUUGCAUGAAAUGGUUCUGAAAGGUAAGAGGAAAACAGACUUUGGAGGUUGUUUAGUUUUGAAUUUCUGACAGAGAUAAAGUAGUUUAAAAUCUCUCGUACACUGAUAACUCAAGCUUUUCAUUUUCUCAUACAGUUGUACAGAUUUAACUGGGACCAUCAGUUUUAAACUGUUGUCAAGCUAACUAAUAAUCAUCUGCUUUAAGACGCAAGAUUCUGAAUUAAACUUUAUAUAGGUAUAGAUACAUCUGUUGUUUCUUUGUAUUUCAGGAAAGGUGAUAGUAGUUUUAUUUGAUACUGAUAAAUAUUGAAUUGAUUUUUUAGUUAUUUUUUAUCAUUUUUUCAAUGGAGUAGUAUAGGACUGUGCUUUGUCCUUUUUAUGAAUGAAAAAAUUAGUAUAAAGUAAUAAAUGUCUUAUGUUACCCAAGAAAGAA